CGAGACCCUAUAUCAAUAAUAAUUAUAAUAAUACAGUAUAUUUUACAUAAUAGACCAUAGAGCUCAAUGAAUCCUCCUCACAACCCUAUGUAGGUAGAUGUUAUCAUGAUCUCUGCUUUCCAGAAUAGAAAAGUGAGGACCAGAGAGGGCGACCUCUUGUCCAAAAGCAAUACAGCCAAGAAGGGGCAAGGAGGGUUUUGAAACCAGUCGGCCAGGCUCUGGGGCUCCUAACAAGCAAAGCAGCCUGGUUUCUAAAACUAUAGCUUCUGGAAGCAGCCAAUUCACAGGUCUUUACCUCCUGACUGUGAGACCUCCAAAAAAUGACCAGGGAUCUUGGAGUCUGUUUCCCCCUUUGUGAACUGGGGACAAUAGAAGCUACUUCCCAGGUCUGCGGGGAGAAAUUAGGAACGAAGAAGGUAAAGCGCAGAGCUGAGGAGCUGGUCUACAGGUGCUCUAUACAUAUUAGUAAUAAUUAUUAAGUUUGCUGUUACAAUCCUCUCUCUCUCUGUGAACAACCCCUAAUGAUGCGUGGCUUUGAGAGCAAAAAAGUCAGGGCAAAGUUUUGCCACAAAGUCCAGAGGGCAAGACAUUAAAUCUAACUCUCAAGGAUUGGUGUUGGCAAGAAAGCAAACCUCUCCUCCCCACGCUGUCCUUACCCCGCGUAUCCGACGAGCCUAAAGUCAUAGGUGGUGGCGGUGGCGGCCCGCGAUCUGAGCCGUGCGAAGGAGUUUGCACAGAAACACGACAUCCCCAAGGCCUACGGCUCCUAUGAGGAGCUGGCCAAGGACCCGAGCGUGGAGGUGGCCUACAUUGGCACCCAGCACCCCCAGCACAAGGCGGCGGUGAUGCUGUGCUUGGCGGCGGGCAAGGCCGUUCUGUGCGAGAAGCCCACGGGCGUGAACGCGGCGGAAGUUCGCGAGAUGGUCGCGGAGGCCCGAUCCCGAGCCCUCUUCCUUAUGGAGGCCAUCUGGACCCGCUUCUUUCCUGCCUCCGAGGCUCUGAGGUCUGUUUUGGCCCAGGGAACUCUAGGAGACCUCCGGGUGGCUCGGGCAGAAUUUGGGAAGAAUCUCAUCCACGUUCCCCGGGCCGUAGACCGGGCCCAGGCUGGGGGGGCCCUGCUGGACAUCGGCAUCUACUGUGUCCAGUUCACCUCCAUGGUCUUUGGAGGGCAGAAGCCAGAGAAGAUUUCUGUCGUGGGAAGGCGUCAUGAAACAGGUGUGGAUGACACUGUCACGGUGCUCCUGCAGUACCCAGGGGAGGUCCAUGGCAGCUUCACCUGCAGCAUCACCGUGCAGCUCUCCAACACGGCCUCCGUGAGCGGCACCAAGGGCAUGGUACAGCUCCUCAACCCCUGCUGGUGCCCGACCGAGCUGGUGGUGAAGGGGGAGCAUAAGGAGUUCCCGCUGCCCCCAGUCCCAAAGGACUGCAAUUUUGACAACGGGGCAGGCAUGAGUUAUGAGGCCAAGCACGUCUGGGAGUGCCUACGCAAGGGUAUGAAGGAAAGUCCUGUGAUUCCCCUGUCGGAAAGUGAGCUCCUGGCUGACAUCCUUGAAGAGGUGAGGAAGGCCAUUGGAGUCACCUUCCCCCAAGACAAACGCUGAUGUAUCCCCGAAUAAAUAAAGACAUCUUACAUCUUC